AGAGAGGCUUGAGGUUCGGGUAGUCGGUGACAUGGCGGAGGCCGCGGCGCUGGUGUGGAUUCGCGGCCCUGGCUUCGGGUGCAAGGCGGUGCGGUGUGCCUCGGGUCGGUGCACCGUCCGGGAUUUUAUCCACCGGCACUGCCAAGAUCAGAAUGUUCCAGUGGAAAACUUCUUUGUGAAAUGCAAUGGAGCACUCAUUAACACCAGUGACACAGUGCAGCAUGGAGCUGUUUAUAGUUUGGAACCCAGACUUUGCGGUGGAAAAGGAGGUUUUGGAUCUAUGCUCCGAGCACUUGGUGCUCAGAUUGAGAAGACAACCAAUCGAGAAGCUUGUCGGGAUCUCAGUGGAAGGAGACUACGCGAUGUCAAUCAUGAAAAAGCAAUGGCUGAAUGGGUAAAACAACAAGCCGAGCGAGAGGCUGAAAAGGAGCAGAAGCGGCUGGAGCGACUGCAGCGGAAGCUUGUAGAACCCAAGCACUGCUUCACCAGCCCCGACUACCAGCAGCAGUGCCAUGAGAUGGCUGAGCGUCUGGAGGAUUCCGUCCUCAAAGGUAUGCAGGCUGCCUCCAGCAAGAUGGUUUCAGCAGAAAUCAGUGAGAAUCGGAAACGGCAAUGGCCUACUAAAUCUCAAACAGACAGAGGAGCCAGUGCGGGAAAGAGGAGAUGCUUCUGGUUGGGCAUGGAGGGACUAGAGACUGCAGAAGGGUCCAACUCUGAGAGUUCAGAUGAUGACAGUGAAGAAGCACCAAGCACUUCAGGAAUGGGUUUCCAUGCUCCAAAAAUUGGUAGCAAUGGUGUCGAGAUGGCAGCCAAAUUUCCCAGUGGUUCUCAGAGGGCGAGAGUAGUGAAUACAGACCAUGGAUCACCAGAACAACUGCAGAUCCCGGUGACUGACUCUGGGAGGCAUAUUUUAGAAGACUCAUGUGCUGAGCUGGGGGAGUCCAAAGAGCACAUGGAAAGCAGGAUGGUUACAGAAACAGAAGAGACCCAGGAGAAGAAGGCAGAGAGUAAAGAACCCAUAGAAGAGGAGCCCACUGGGGCUGGACUGAAUAAGGAUAAAGAGACAGAAGAAAGGACUGAUGGGGAAAGAGUUGCUGAGGUAGCACCUGAAGAAAGGGAAAACGUUGCCGUUGCCAAACUGCAGGAAAGCCAGCCAGGAAACGCAGUUAUUGAUAAGGAAACUAUAGAUUUAUUGGCGUUCACCUCUGUUGCAGAACUGGAGUUGCUGGGUUUGGAGAAGCUCAAAUGUGAACUGAUGGCCCUUGGACUGAAAUGUGGGGGCACUCUGCAGGAGCGGGCAGCAAGACUCUUCUCUGUCAGAGGACUGGCAAAGGAGCAAAUUGACCCGGCUUUAUUUGCCAAGCCUUUGAAAGGGAAGAAAAAAUGAGUAUCAUCAGAGCUGAUUCCUAUUUGUUUAUAGUGUCUACCAUUUACAACCUGCAUAAUGUGGACUCUUGACCAGUAUUCCUGUUGAUAUUAAAAGCUAACUUUUUAGUAACCCAAUUCUAACUAUCCCCUUUUUCCUUGUCAGGGCUGUAGAAUUAAUGUCUGAAACCAUCUGGGCCUUAAAUUUUCUUUGUCUGGUUUUCUAUAGUGUAUUUAAUAAAUAUAGGGCUAUUCACAUUUUUUGGUUUGAUCUUGGUGUCAUUUAGGUAAUGAAUCUAUCCAAGAAAUCUAUCCUUUUGACCCAGGUUAUCAAAUUUGUAGACAUAAGGUUAUUUAUAAUGGUCCCUUCUUACCCUUUUAAUGUCUUUAGGAGCUGUGUUGAUAAUUUCCUUUUCAUUAUGAUACUGGUAAUUUCUGUUCUCACUUUCCUAAUCAGGUUGGGUAGGGGUUUAUCAGUUUUACUGAUCUGACUUUUUAUUUUAUUUUAUUUUUUUUGAGACAGUCUUACACUGUCUCCCAGGCUGGAGUGCAGUGGCGCGAUCUCGGCUUACUGCAAGCUCUGCCUUCCGGGUUCAUGCCAUUCUCCUGCCUCAGCCUCCCCAGUAGCUGGGACUACAGGCUCCCACCACCACGCCCGGCUAAUUUUUUAUAUUUUUAGUGGAGACUGGGUUUCACUGUGUUAGCCAGGAUGGUCUCGAUCUCUUUACCUCGUGGUCCACCCGCCUCAGCCUCCCAGAGUGCUGGGAUUACAGGCGUGAGCCACCGUGCCUGGCCGACGAUAUAACUUUUAAAGAACCAACCUUUGGUUUUAUUUUUCUCAAUUGUUUAUAUAAUUAAUUUCUGUUAUUUUCUUUCUUCUAUUUAGCUUGAGUCUCCUUUGAUCUUUUUUCUUUAGUUCCUUAAGAUAAGCCUUAGGUCAUUGAUCUUAGACGUUAUUUAAAAUACAUAUUUAAAGCUAUACAUUUUCUUUUAAGCAUUACUUUAGUUGCGACUUUACAAUUUUAUUAUGUCGUAUUUUUAUUAUUCAGUUCUAAUUUUCUUUUUUUUUUCUUUUUGAGAUGGAAUUUCGCUUUUGUUGCCCAGGCUAGAGUGCAAUGGUACGAUCUCAGCUCACUGCAACCUCUGCCUCCUGGGUUCAAGCGAUUCUCCUGCCUCAGCCUCCUCAGUAGCUGGGAUUACAGGCUCCAGCCACCAUACCUGGCUGAUUUUUGUAUUUUUAGUAGAGAUGGGGUUUCACCACAUUGGCCAGGCUGGUCUCGAACUCCUGACCUCAGGUGAUCCACCCACUUUGGCCUCCCAAAGUGCUGGGAUUACAGGUGUGAGCCACCAUGCCCAGCCUCUGAUUAUUUUCUAAUUUCCUCCCUCAGUUCUUCUUUGACCCAUGGAUUAUCAGAAGUGGGUUGUCUGAUCAGCAAACAUUUGUUUUUUUUCCUCUUAAUAUCUUCUUGUUGCUGAUUUCUACUUUAAUUCCAUUGAGGUCAGAAAAUAUCCUCUUUAUGAUUUCAAUCCUCUUAGUUUUAUUGAGACUCGUUUUAUGACCCAAUAUGUUGUCUGUCAUGGUGAGUGUACCAUACACAGUUUAAAAGAAUGCGUAUUUUAGGCCAGGUGUGGUGGCUCAUGCCUGUAAUCCAGCAUGAGAUUACAUGCUGAGAUUACAGCUGUAAUCUGUAAUUUGAGAGGCUGAGGUGGGAGGAUCAUUUCGAGACCAGCCUGGGCAAUGUAUAGUGAGACCAUGUCUCUAAGAAAAACAAUAUGUAAUUUGAAUUGUUGGGUUAAUAUGUUUUGUAAUAUCGAUGAGAUUAAGUGGUUGAUAGUAUUGUUCAGAUCUUCUAUGUCUUUACUGAUCCUUUUGUUUAUUUCUAUCAGGUGCUGAGAAAGGAUGUUAAAAUCUUCAAUUAUGAUUGUGGAAUUGUCUAUUUCUUAAAUUCUACCAGUUUUUGUAUGAAGCUCUAAUAACUUAUGUCUUCCUAAUGUAUUGACCAUUUUAUCAUUAUGAAAUUUCCCUCUGUCUCUGGUAAUUUGGGUUUGAAAUCUACUUUAUCUUAUGUGAAUAUAGCCACUGCAGCCUUCUUAAGCUUAGUGUUUGCACAGUAUACCUCUUUCUAUUAAUUUACUUUGUGCUUCUGUGCCUAUUUAAAGUAGUUUCUUUAAACAACAUAUACUUGAGACUUGCAUUUUUAUCUGUUCUCUCUGUAUCUUUUAAUAAGUUUAACAUUAAAUGUAAUUAUUAAUAGGUUUCUAAUUUACAUGUUUCCUGUUUAGAUAAGAUUAUUUUAUAAUUGUAUUUUAAUUUAUUGGCUCUUUAGCUAUACUGUUUUAAUAAUUUUUUUAAGUUGGAUGUUCUAGUGAUUACAAUAUACAUUCUUAAUUUUUCAGUCUACCUAGAGUUGAUGUGCCACUUCACAUAAAAUGUAGAAAUCUUGUAAGUAUGUACAUCCAUUUAUCAUACCUGUCUUUUAUGCUGUAGUUGUCAUACAUAUUAAAUCUACAUAUUUAAAUAUUGUAAGUCCUGUCAUAAGUUACAAUUUCUGCUUUAAAUAAUGAUAUGUAUUUUAAAGAAAUUAAGAGGAAAAAAUAAAAUCUUUUGUAUUUAUUCACAUA